CGGGAAGCCGGGAAGCGGGGAUUCCAUUCGACUCCGGAGAGGGGGACUCCGCUUUCGAAUGGAGAGCCGGGACCUUGGCGUCUGGGCCCCGCGGAAGAUCGGGAGCCAGCGGGCGCGGUGGCUCACGCCUGUGAUCCCAGCACUUUGGGAGGGGGAGUUCGAGACCAGCCUGGGUGACACAGCGAGACUCUCGCUCAAAAUAAAAAUAGUCCACCUUCUCCAAUCCCUGCCUGCUGGGAGAGGACGAUCUCUUGAGAAAGGAAAGACUUCUGUGCUCCCGAGAACUUCCUAUCAGGUCCUGGCUGCAGGGAAACAAGCUGGGCUUUUUAUAAUUAAGGUUGGAAGAAGUCACCACAGGCAGCAGAACUCCAUCUUGAGAUGAAAUAACAUCUACCUGGACCUCUGGCAGAAUUUCAAGGCACACACUGGGCUGACUCUGGCGCCAUGAUGUUGCCUUAUCCUUCAGCACUGGGAGAUCAAUACUGGGAAGAGAUUUUGCUUCCAAAGAAUGGGGAAAAUGUAGAGACUAUGAAGAAAUUGACCCAAAAUCAUAAAGCGAAAGGCUUGCCUUCUAAUGAUACUGACUGCCCCCAGAAAAAGGAGGGAAAGGCCCAAAUAGUGGUACCAGUUACAUUCAGGGAUGUGACUGUGAUCUUCACAGAAGCAGAAUGGAAGAGACUGAGUCCAGAGCAGAGGAAUCUAUACAAAGAAGUGAUGCUGGAGAAUUACAGGAAUCUUCUCUCAUUGGAUGGAGUUUCGCUCUUGUUGCCCAGGCUAGAGUGCAAUCGUGCAAUCUCGGCUCACCACAACCUUUGCCUCCCGGGUUCAAGCAAUUCUCCUGCCACAGCCUCUCGAGUAGUUGGGAUUACAGAACCAAAGCCAGAAAUCUACACUUGUUCCUCCUGCCUUCUGGCCUUCUCCUGUCAGCAGUUCCUCAGUCAACAUGUACUUCAGAUCUUCCUGGGCUUAUGUGCAGAAAAUCACUUCCAUCCAGGGAAUUCUAGCCCAGGGCAUUGGAAACAGCAGGGGCAGCAGUAUUCCCAUGUAAGCUGUUGGUUUGAAAAUGCAGAAGGUCAGGAGAGAGGAGGUGGCUCCAAACCCUGGUCUGCAAGGACAGAGGAGAGAGAAACCUCAAGGGCAUUCCCCAGCCCACUCCAAAGACAGUCAGCAAGUCCUAGAAAAGGCAACAUGGUGGUAGAAACAGAGCCCAGCUCAGCCCAAAGACCAAACCCUGUGCAGCUAGACAAAGGCUUGAAGGAAUUAGAAACCUUGAGAUUUGGAGCAAUCAACUGUAGAGAGUAUGAACCGGACCAUAACCUGGAAUCAAACUUUAUUACAAACCCGAGGACCCUCUUAGGGAAGAAGCCCUACAUUUGCAGUGAUUGUGGGCGAAGCUUUAAAGAUAGAUCAACCCUCAUCAGACACCAUCGUAUACACUCGAUGGAGAAGCCUUAUGUGUGCAGUGAGUGCGGGCGAGGUUUUAGCCAGAAGUCCAACCUCAGCAGACACCAGAGAACACAUUCAGAAGAGAAGCCUUAUUUGUGCAGGGAGUGUGGGCAAAGCUUUAGAAGUAAGUCCAUCCUCAAUAGACAUCAGUGGACUCACUCAGAGGAGAAGCCCUAUGUUUGCAGCGAGUGUGGGCGAGGCUUUAGCGAGAAGUCAUCCUUCAUCAGACACCAGAGGACACACUCCGGUGAGAAACCCUAUGUGUGCCUGGAGUGUGGACGAAGCUUUUGUGAUAAGUCAACCCUCAGAAAACACCAGAGGAUACACUCAGGGGAGAAGCCUUAUGUUUGCAGGGAGUGUGGGCGAGGCUUUAGCCAGAACUCAGAUCUCAUCAAACACCAGAGGACACACUUGGAUGAGAAGCCUUAUGUUUGCAGGGAGUGUGGGCGAGGCUUUUGUGACAAGUCAACCCUCAUCAUACACGAGCGGACGCACUCUGGAGAGAAGCCUUAUGUGUGUGGUGAGUGUGGCCGAGGCUUUAGUCGGAAAUCACUCCUCCUUGUCCACCAGAGGACACACUCAGGGGAGAAGCAUUAUGUCUGCAGGGAGUGUAGGCGAGGUUUUAGCCAGAAGUCAAAUCUCAUCAGACACCAGAGGACGCACUCAAAUGAGAAGCCUUAUAUUUGCAGGGAAUGUGGGCGAGGCUUUUGUGACAAGUCAACCCUCAUUGUACAUGAGAGGACACACUCAGGAGAGAAGCCUUACGUGUGCAGUGAGUGUGGCCGAGGCUUUAGCCGGAAAUCACUCCUCCUUGUCCACCAGAGGACACACUCAGGGGAGAAGCAUUAUGUUUGUAGGGAGUGUGGGCGAGGCUUUAGUCAUAAGUCAAAUCUCAUCAGACACCAGAGGACACACUGACGGGAGAAACCUGUGUAUGCAGGGGUCAUGAACAAGACCUGAGUGACCAGUCAAGCCUCAUGUUACCCCAGAGAGACACAUGGGGAGUAGACCCUGUGUACACAGAUUGUGAGUGAAGUUCCAGAGAUGUGUCAGCCCUUAUCAGGCAUGGGAGGGACACGUUCAGGAGAGGAGCCUUAUGAGUAUAGAGUACGGGCAACUGUAGCCAUCAGUCAGCCUUGAGCAUGCACAAAAGGACACACUUAGGAGAGAAGUUUAUGUGUAGGGACUGUGGGAAGGCUUUAGCAAUAAUCAACAUUUACCAGACAUCCAAUGACAGCCUCAGGGGAAAGCACCCUUGUCUGGGGAGUGUUGGGGAGCAUCAGUAAAAGAAUGGACACUCAGGCACAGAGUGGCCCUCAGGAAGGAGGUCUUUGUUUGUAGGAUGUAUGGGCAAAGCUUUUGUGAUCACACACCACAGGGAGAAUCUGCAUGUGGGGACACUGUGGAGCUCUGCCCAGAUGACCUUUUCAGGGGUAACACCCCAGCUGCUUGAGAGAACAGUGUUGCUGCUGGCAGAGAUGCAUUCCAGAGAUGCACUCCGCUCUGGAACUCACUCUCAGCCACAGGGAGCUGCAUGCACCACAGGGGCAAUGCACCUUUGCAGGGGUACCUUCUGGCCCCAACCCUUGACUCAACGGGGACAACUCCAGAAGGUCAUUCCAGAUCCAGAGAUCCCCAUCGAACUGAAGGAUCACUGGGUUGCAGACACAUUGCAGGUCAGCUUCUUCCUCUGCCCAGUCCUGCCCUCACUCCCCAGUGAAUCCUCAAUUUUCUGUCUCGUUGUCUGUCCAGAUAAUUGAUUCUAAGACAUGUUAGGUAUAUAAGGAGUGUAGAUAAGGCUUCAGCCAUGAGUCACCCCGCAGUAAGCCCCAGAGUAUAUUGAAUAGAAAUUCUGCAUGUGUGGGGAGAAUGGACAAGGACUUAGGAAAAAGUCCUCAUCAAAGAACAGCUUUUUUGGGACAAGCUUUACAUGGGUGGGGAGGGAAAAUGUGAAACACAUUAGCAAUAAGUUAAACCUCAUCUUGUACUAAAGGAGGACACACUCAGGGAGAAGACCUCUGUGGGCAGGGCUUGUGGGUGGAGCUUCAUCCCGAUGUCACUCCUCAACUGACUUAGGAGGACAGUCUUGCUACCCCAAGUCACUACCUCACUCACCUCUGAGGGAUUUUCAGGAAAUGUCUUGACUCCCCCAUGUACUCUGUAUGUGAGCGAAGAUGGCAGUAACUGUUAAAUAAGCAUUCUUUUCUACUUCUUGGAAUCAGAUGAAAUAAAAAAGCAGGCUUUAUUUAAGUAAUCAAAAAA